CUCAGGACUCUGCGAGACAGCCUCAGUGGCUGGGACCCGGAGACCCUGGCCCUCCUGCUGAGGGAGGAGCUGCAGGCCUACAAGGCGGUGCGGGCCGACACUGGACAGGAACGCUUCAACAUCAUCUGUGACCUCCUGGAGCUGAGCCCCGAGGAGACACCAGCCGGGGCCUGGGCACGAGCCACCCACCUGGUAGAACUGGCUCAGGUGCUCUGCUACCACGACUUUACGCAGCAGACCAACUGCUCUGCUCUGGAUGCUAUCCGGGAAGCCCUGCAGCUUCUGGACUCUGUGAGGCCUGAGGCCCAGGCCAGAGAUCAGCUUCUGGACGAUAAAGCACAGGCCUUGCUGUGGCUUUACAUCUGUACUCUGGAAGCCAAAAUGCAGGAAGGUAUCGAGCGGGAUCGGAGAGCCCAGGCCCCUGGUAACUUGGAGGAAUUUGAAGUCAAUGACCUGAACUAUGAAGAUAAACUCCAGGAAGAUCGUUUCCUAUACAGUAACAUUGCCUUCAACCUGGCUGCAGAUGCUGCUCAGUCCAAAUGCCUGGACCAAGCCCUGGCCCUGUGGAAGGAGCUGCUUACAAAGGGGCAGGCCCCAGCUGUACGGUGUCUCCAGCAGACAGCAGCCUCACUGCAGAUCCUAGCAGCCCUCUACCAGCUGGUGGCAAAGCCCAUGCAGGCUCUGGAGGUCCUCCUGCUGCUACGGAUUGUCUCUGAGAGACUGAAGGACCACUCGAAGGCAGCUGGCUCCUCCUGCCACAUCACCCAGCUCCUCCUGACCCUCGGCUGUCCCAGCUAUGCCCAGUUACACCUGGAAGAGGCAGCAUCGAGCCUGAAGCAUCUCGAUCAGACUACUGACACAUACCUGCUCCUUUCCCUGACCUGUGAUCUGCUUCGAAGUCAACUCUACUGGACUCACCAGAAGGUGACCAAGGGUGUCUCUCUGCUGCUGUCUGUGCUUCGGGAUCCUGCCCUCCAGAAGUCCUCCAAGGCUUGGUACUUGCUGCGUGUCCAGGUCCUGCAGCUGGUGGCAGCUUACCUUAGCCUCCCGUCAAACAACCUCUCACACUCCCUGUGGGAGCAGCUCUGUGCCCAAGGCUGGCAGACACCUGAGAUAGCUCUCAUAGACUCCCAUAAGCUCCUCCGAAGCAUCAUCCUCCUGCUGAUGGGCAGUGACAUUCUCUCAACUCAGAAAGCAGCUGUGGAGACAUCGUUUUUGGACUAUGGUGAAAAUCUGGUACAAAAAUGGCAGGUUCUUUCAGAGGUGCUGAGCUGCUCAGAGAAGCUGGUCUGCCACCUGGGCCGCCUGGGUAGUGUGAGUGAAGCCAAGGCCUUUUGCUUGGAGGCCCUAAAACUUACAACAAAGCUGCAGAUACCACGCCAGUGUGCCCUGUUCCUGGUGCUGAAGGGCGAGCUGGAGCUGGCCCGCAAUGACAUUGAUCUCUGUCAGUCGGACCUGCAGCAGGUUCUGUUCUUGCUUGAGUCUUGCACAGAGUUUGGUGGGGUGACUCAGCACCUGGACUCUGUGAAGAAGGUCCACCUGCAGAAGGGGAAGCAGCAGGCCCAGGUCCCCUGUCCUCCACAGCUCCCAGAGGAGGAGCUCUUCCUAAGAGGCCCUGCUCUAGAGCUGGUGGCCACUGUGGCCAAGGAGCCUGGCCCCAUAGCACCUUCUACAAACUCCUCCCCAGUCUUGAAAACCAAGCCCCAGCCCAUACCCAACUUCCUGUCCCAUUCACCCACCUGUGACUGCUCGCUCUGCGCCAGCCCUGUCCUCACAGCAGUCUGUCUGCGCUGGGUAUUGGUCACGGCAGGGGUGAGGCUGGCCAUGGGCCACCAAGCCCAGGGUCUGGAUCUGCUGCAGGUCGUGCUGAAGGGCUGUCCUGAAGCCGCUGAGCGCCUCACCCAAGCUCUCCAAGCUUCCCUGAAUCAUAAAACACCCCCCUCCUUGGUUCCAAGCCUCUUGGAUGAGAUCUUGGCUCAAGCAUACACACUGUUGGCACUGGAGGGCCUGAACCAGCCAUCAAACGAGAGCCUGCAGAAGGUUCUACAGUCAGGGCUGAAGUUUGUAGCAGCACGGAUACCCCACCUAGAGCCCUGGCGAGCCAGCCUGCUCUUGAUUUGGGCCCUCACAAAACUAGGUGGCCUCAGCUGCUGUACUACCCAACUUUUUGCAAGCUCCUGGGGCUGGCAGCCACCAUUAAUAAAAAGUGUCCCUGGCUCAGAGCCCUCUAAGACUCAGGGCCAAAAACGUUCUGGACGAGGGCGCCAAAAGUUAGCCUCUGCUCCCCUGCGCCUCAAUAAUACCUCUCAGAAAGGUCUGGAAGGUAGAGGACUGCCCUGCACACCUAAACCCCCAGACCGGAUCAGGCAAGCUGGCCCUCAUGUCCCCUUCACGGUGUUUGAGGAAGUCUGCCCUACAGAGAGCAAGCCUGAAGUACCCCAGGCCCCCAGGGUACAACAGAGAGUCCAGACGCGCCUCAAGGUGAACUUCAGUGAUGACAGUGACUUGGAAGACCCUGUCUCAGCUGAGGCCUGGCUGGCAGAGGAGCCUAAGAGACGGGGCACUGCUUCCCGGGGCCGGGGGCGAGCAAGGAAGGGCCUGAGCCUAAAGACGGAUGCCGUGGUUGCCCCAGGUAGUGCCCCUGGGAACCCUGGCCUGAAUGGCAGGAGCCGGAGGGCCAAGAAGGUGGCAUCAAGACAUUGUGAGGAGCGGCGUCCCCAGAGGGCCAGUGACCAGGCCAGGCCUGGCCCUGAGAUCAUGAGGACCAUCCCUGAGGAAGAACUGACUGACAACUGGAGAAAAAUGAGCUUUGAGAUCCUCAGGGGCUCUGACGGGGAAGACUCAGCCUCAGGUGGGAAGACUCCAGCUCCGGGCCCUGAGGCAGCUUCUGGAGAAUGGGAGCUGCUGAGGCUGGAUUCCAGCAAGAAGAAGCUGCCCAGCCCAUGCCCAGACAAGGAGAGUGACAAGGACCUUGGUCCUCGGCUCCGGCUCCCCUCAGCCCCCGUAGCCACUGGUCUUUCUACCCUGGACUCCAUCUGUGACUCCCUGAGUGUUGCUUUCCGGGGCAUUAGUCACUGUCCUCCUAGUGGGCUCUAUGCCCACCUCUGCCGCUUCCUGGCCUUGUGCCUGGGCCACCGGGAUCCUUAUGCCACUGCUUUCCUUGUCACCGAGUCUGUCUCCAUCACCUGUCGCCACCAGCUGCUCACCCACCUCCACAGACAGCUCAGCAAGGCCCAGAAGCACCGAGGAUCACUUGAAAUAGCAGACCAGCUGCAGGGGCUGAGCCUUCAGGAGAUGCCUGGAGAUGUCCCCCUGGCCCGCAUCCAGCGCCUCUUUUCCUUCAGGGCUUUGGAAUCUGGCCACUUCCCCCAGCCUGAAAAGGAGAGUUUCCAGGAGCGCCUGGCUCUGAUCCCCAGUGGGGUGACUGUGUGUGUGUUGGCCCUGGCCACCCUCCAGCCCGGAACCGUGGGCAACACCCUCCUGCUGACCCGGCUGGAAAAGGACAGUCCCCCAGUCAGUGUGCAGAUUCCCACUGGCCAGAACAAGCUUCAUCUGCGUUCAGUCCUGAAUGAGUUUGAUGCCAUCCAGAAGGCACAGAAAGAGAACAGCAGCUGUACUGACAAGCGAGAAUGGUGGACAGGGCGGCUGGCACUGGACCACAGGAUGGAGGUUCUCAUCGCUUCCCUAGAGAAGUCUGUGCUGGGCUGCUGGAAGGGGCUGCUGCUGCCGUCCAGUGAGGAGCCCGGCCCUGCCCAGGAGGCCUCCCGCCUACAGGAGCUGCUACAGGACUGUGGCUGGAAAUAUCCUGACCGCACUCUGCUGAAAAUCAUGCUCAGUGGUGCCGGUGCCCUCACCCCUCAGGACAUUCAGGCCCUGGCCUACGGGCUGUGCCCAACCCAGCCAGAGCGAGCCCAGGAGCUCCUGAAUGAGGCAGUAGGACGUCUACAGGGCCUGACAGUACCAAGCAAUAGCCACCUUGUCUUGGUCCUAGACAAGGACUUGCAGAAGCUGCCGUGGGAAAGCAUGCCCAGCCUCCAAGCACUGCCUGUCACCCGGCUGCCCUCCUUCCGCUUCCUACUCAGCUACUCCAUCAUCAAAGAGUAUGGGGCCUCGCCAGUGCUGAGUCAAGGGGUGGAUCCACGAAGUACCUUCUAUGUCCUGAACCCUCACAAUAACCUGUCAAGCACAGAGGAGCAAUUUCGAGCCAAUUUCAGCAGUGAAGCUGGCUGGAGAGGAGUGGUUGGGGAGGUGCCAAGACCUGAACAGGUGCAGGAAGCCCUGACAAAGCAUGAUUUGUAUAUCUAUGCAGGGCAUGGGGCUGGUGCCCGCUUCCUUGAUGGGCAGGCUGUCCUGCGGCUGAGCUGUCGGGCAGUGGCCCUGCUGUUUGGCUGUAGCAGUGCGGCCCUGGCUGUGCGUGGAAACCUGGAGGGGGCUGGCAUCGUGCUCAAGUACAUCAUGGCUGGUUGCCCCUUGUUUCUGGGUAAUCUCUGGGAUGUGACUGACCGCGACAUUGACCGCUACACGGAAGCUCUGCUGCAAGGCUGGCUUGGAGCAGGCCCAGGGGCCCCCCUUCUCUACUAUGUAAACCAGGCCCGCCAAGCUCCCCGACUCAAGUAUCUUAUUGGGGCUGCACCUAUAGCCUAUGGCUUGCCUGUCUCUCUGCGGUAACCCCAUGGAGCUGUCUUAUUGAUGCUAGAAGCCUCAUAACUGUUCUACCUCCAAGGUUAGAUUUAAUCCUUAGGAUAACUCUUUUAAAGUGAUUUUCCCCAGUGUUUUAUAUGAAACAUUUCCUUUUGAUUUAACCUCAGUAUAAUAAAGAUACAUCAUUUAAA